CAAUUACUUGCUAAGAGCAAACUUGAAGGUAUGGAUAAGGCCCUGAGUCAUCUUCCUGAGCUGAAUGAUAGUUAAGCUGAAUUUCAAUAACUAUAAUUUCUCUGCUGUGCAAUCAAAUACUAGAACUUCUUCCUUCGAACGCUAUAUCCCUAAUUCAAUAACAAGUAAACUGAAGCUCAGCAUGGUCUAGGAACUUUGUUACGUUAACACAGCAAGUGAGUGUUGCAGCCUGGAUCCAAAAAUCAGGCCUGGUCGACCUCAAAGUCCAGAUUAUUGACCUUUCUACCAUAAUGUAUGGAGGAAUUAGAGAAAGAACAAAUCAGUGUGAAGGAGAAUUGUCAGUAAAAUUACAAGAAAAGAUUGAGAUCAUAAUUGACCUUUGAGGAUAAUAAAAUUUAAAGACCAAAAGGAUGGACUUCACAGAAACAUGACCUUAGGUUGUUUUUGCAGUUGUAGUAACUGGUUAUAUGACCAACAAAAUAUGAAGAAUGGGUACAAAUUCUGAUAGUAAUGAUCAGUCACUUUGCAAAUAUAAAGUUACUAUUUACUACUGUAUUGUACAGGUUCAAUAAUCUUUGUGUACACAUUUUAUGUAUUUAUUGUCAGGCUGCUAUAUAAUUCAGUAUUUAUAAUAGAUACUAUGUAUAGCAAUCUAUGGUUAGUUUUGGUCUUAACCAGGAAAAAUCACUCUUUUGAGUUUUGCUGUUUUUACUAGAUUAUUUUUACUGGAUGAUUGCUCAUAUUAUUUGAUUAUUAUUGCAAUUUGUCUUUCUGGAAUAGGAAGCAAGAGGCCUGAAUUCUGGUUCCUAUUCUAUCAAUUGUGUGAAUUCUGGAAACUCAGUUUACUUUUCUGGGCCUCAUGGUUUUCAUCUGAAUGAUGACCAACUUGGAUAAAAUGGUCUUUAUAUAAUUUCGUAGGCAUUUCCCUUCCCAAGGGCUUGAGUCUUUUUCAACAAUUAUAGAGUUUUCCGGUCCCUCUUCCCAGUGCCUCAGCACCUUGCUAUUCAUGUUCAUCUGAUCAGUUGUUUGCAUGCUGACUUACAUUACCCUGAUGGGCAGUACCUGUGGCUGUUUCUGCUCCCUCACCCAGUCCAUAGGCUUCUGGUUGUAAAAAGUGUGCAUCUUGAGACUGUGGACAGUUAGCUCCAGAGGUGACAGUAUAAUCACUUCACGUAGAAGAGGAUAGAGAGAGACUCAUGCCAGUGGUGGUGAGCAAGUAUUAGAGAUAUGAUGUGUGCCUCUGUGAGUUUUGGGGUCUAAGAUAAAUUAUGGCACUAGGAAGAUGGUCCUUUGUGUCAGAAGAACUGGAGUUGUUGGUGCAAAAAAGUAUGAUGUCAGCAUAGCAGUUUUAUUUGUACCUCAGCAACUUCUAAAAUAAUCUCUAUUAAGUGUUUUCAGGAACUACUUUCUACUAUAGGAAAAUGAUUGAGGUGAGUAUCCAUCUGGACACAGAGAAAUAUAACACUGUUUUCUGCUCACCCUCCACUUCACAUAUAAAUACAAUAUGUGUUAAAGGACUAAAUUUCUAGUGUCACAGUUUGUACUUUAUAGUUUGAAGUCAAUAAGAAAGCUCAUAUACCUUCCUAAAAGUCACUUGUUAAUGUUUGAUAUUAAUCUAAUUUUAUCAUAAAUUAAAAGUAUAAAACUACAAAUUUCUUAAAGAUAAAAUAUCCGAAUGGAUUCAGUCAAAUUAAGCAUGAUAAUAUCAAAUAUCAGAAUAGGUUACCAUGCAGGAGGUACUGAGUACUUAAAAGGGUGGGGAAUGCAAUGAACAUAAAAGCUGGUACCAAGGGGAGGAGGAGACAGUGAUGAAUUAAAACAUUAUCUUAACUAAUCCAAGUGCUGGUCUUCAAUACUUUCAUGUGUAUAGACAAAGAGAAACUGCAGAGAUUUCUCACAACCUCUGUGGCCAUUUUAUGCAUGUAUCUUAGCAGAAACACUGGUGAAAUCCCUCCAAAACAUAUUUAUUAGGCAUGGAAAAAGCCUUACAUGACAGGUGGCAUAGGCUCCUUAUGAAAUCAUUGCAGGAUGGGAAGCCAUUUAGGGCUUCGUAAUUGUGAAAGAUUGUAUAGAAACUGAGGCACUUAAAUAGCAGUAAGCAUGAGAAAAUGUGGUAGAUAAUGGUGGUGAUUCUAUUUCUUGUGAAAGUCCACUUACUCUAGUCUGCUACAGUUGUGGGCUUUCCGAUUUCACAUACCCCAGUCUCUAUAUUCUCUCAAUCCACAGCCUACCUCAACUAAGUCUGUCCCAGGCACCUCUUACUGCAGUGAUAAUCCAUCUGUUAAUCAUGUUUUCCUCUUAUGUCUACUUUCUGUCAGAGAAUUGUGGGUGCAAACUGGGAAGGGAAGGAAAUUAUAAGAAUAUGUAUAAGUACAAAUGGAAUAUGUUGGAAAUGAGGAAUAGUUAAUAUCACAGGUCAUUUAAACACCUGAUGAAUUUCAUGGAUAGUCAGGAAUCUUGUUCUUACCUAAUCUGUUAAUUUUAGAUCAGACAUUACACUGAAAGUAUUGAUGAUGGGUUUAAAUCAGGUUGCAGCUCACAUGUUGUGAUAAUAUUAUGUUGAUUUUUUGUUUUUAAUAUGUGAGGAACAGAAUAACUGUAUACUAUUUAUUCAUAGUGACAUUGCAAUAUUGAUUUUAGUACAUAUUAUUAUCUUCAUAAUCACAAUUUCCUCCCCAUUUUCUUAGUUCUCAUAAUUUUAGCCACAGCCCAGUUGGCUGGACCAAUGGAUGGAGAGAAUCACUCAGUGGUAUCUGAGUUUUUGUUUCUGGGACUCACUCAUUCAUGGGAGAUCCAGCUCCUCCUCCUAGUGUUUUCCUCUGUGCUCUAUGUGGCAAGCAUUACUGGAAACAUCCUCAUUGUGUUUUCUGUGACCACUGACCCUCACUUACACUCCCCCAUGUACUUUCUACUGGCCAGUCUCUCCUUCAUUGACUUAGGAGCCUGCUCUGUCACUUCUCCCAAGAUGAUUUAUGACCUGUUCAGAAAGCGCAAAGUCAUCUCCUUUGGAGGCUGCAUCGCUCAAAUCUUCUUCAUCCACGUCGUUGGUGGUGUGGAGAUGGUGCUGCUCAUAGCCAUGGCCUUUGACAGAUAUGUGGCCCUAUGUAAGCCCCUCCACUAUCUGACCAUUAUGAGCCCAAGAAUGUGCCUUUCAUUUCUGGCUGUUGCCUGGACCCUUGGUGUCAGUCACUCCCUGUUCCAACUGGCAUUUCUUGUUAAUUUAGCCUUCUGUGGCCCUAAUGUGUUGGACAGCUUCUACUGUGACCUUCCUCGGCUUCUCAGACUAGCCUGUACCGACACCUACAGAUUGCAGUUCAUGGUCACUGUUAACAGUGGGUUUAUCUGUGUGGGUACUUUCUUCAUACUUCUAAUCUCCUACGUCUUCAUCCUGUUUACUGUUUGGAAACAUUCCUCAGGUGGUUCAUCCAAGGCCCUUUCCACUCUUUCAGCUCACAGCACAGUGGUCCUUUUGUUCUUUGGUCCACCCAUGUUUGUGUAUACACGGCCACACCCUAAUUCACAGAUGGACAAGUUUCUGGCUAUUUUUGAUGCAGUUCUCACUCCUUUUCUGAAUCCAGUUGUCUAUACAUUCAGGAAUAAGGAGAUGAAGGCAGCAAUAAAGAGAGUAUGCAAACAGCUAGUGAUUUACAAGAGGAUCUCAUAAAUGAUAUAAUAAGCCCUUCUCAUUAAACAUGAUAUGGCUUUAUGUUUCUUUCUUUGAUAUUUUAGAUUCAGGAACUAUGAGACAUUAUGUAUUGAUUUGAAUGUUAUUAGACCUGUAACAUAAUUCUUAUCUGAUGAAUAUAUGAUGAAUAUAUUCCUUGUUCAAAAUGAGUCAUAAAUUCAACACAUCUCUACAUCUAUAUUAUGCCCAUUUAAUUUCUUUCAGCAAUGUUUUGUAGUUUUUGGUGAACAGGUACUUUAUGCAUAUGUACUUUAUAUUUAUCUCUAAGUUUUAUAUUUCUGAUGCCCUUUUAAGUGACAUUUUUAUUUCAAUUUACAAUUGUUUAUUCUUAGCUUAUGGGCACAUAAUAGAUCUUUGUUUGACAUUAUAUCCUGUAAACUUGCAAAACUUAUAAGUUCCAUCAGUUUUUUAUAGGUUAUGUAGGAUUUUCUUUAUAGAUGAUUAUGUUGUCAGUGAAUAAAGACAUUUGCUUUUAAAAUUCUAGUAUGAAUUCACUAUAUUCAUUUUGUUGAAUGCUGAGUAGAAUUAGUUAGAGUAGACAUCUUUGACUUGUUCCUGUUAUGAAAUAUAUUAAAUAUUUCAUCAUUAAGUAUAAUGUUAGCUAUAAUUUUUUUCAUAGGUACUCUUUAACAGGCUGAGAAAGUUUUCUGUAUUCACAGUUUGCUGAAAAUUUCUUUUAUCUUUAGUCAGGAAUGGAUCUUGGAUUUUGUAAAGCUUUUUCGUUUCAGAAUCAGGGUAAUGCUGGCCCUUUAGAAUGAGUUGGGAAGCAUCUGCUCUUCUUAAAUUUUCUGCCAUAAUUUUGUAGAAUUCAUAUAAUUUUUUUCUUUAAAAAGGGAAGUACUUAAGUAUUUUUUCCCAUAAGUUACCCAUAAGUAAAUCUAAAGGAAAGUGGGAAACUUUGAUACGCAUUGGUUGCCCCCUGGUGGAGAUUUCUGGGUUCUUGAUUAUUUUAACACUGGAGAUAGAAUCUGGUGGAAUGACGUCAAUGCUACCGUGAUUAAGAGGUGUGUAGGAAAUGCUUCAUGUAAAAGAGAAAAUAGUCUUUAUGAGAAUCUGCCUGGUGGAAAGGAGUUGGUGCAACAAUAACAAUAUAAAUUAGUGAAAAAUUUUAAAUUGACAAAUAAUAAUUGUAUCUAUUUAUGGGGUACAAUGUAAUGUUUUGAUACAUGUUUAAAUUGUGGAAAGAUUAGGUCUAUCUUAUUGACAUACAUAUCUUUUUUGUGGUGAAAACAUUUAAAAUCUACUCUGUUAGUCAUUUUGAAACAUACAAUACCUUGUUAUUUAUUACAGUCACCAUUCUGUGCAAUAGUUCACUGAAACUUUGUCUAACUGAAACUUUGAACCCUUUUAUCAACAUCUACCUUUUCCAUGUCUACCCCCAACUACUAGCCUCUGAUAAUCACCAUUCCAUUCUCUACUUCUAUGAAUUCAACUUUUUUAGAUUCCACAUAUCAGUGAGAUCAUGUGAUAUUUGUCUUUUCGUGCCUGGCUUAUUUCACUUAGCGUGAUAUCUUCUGGGUUAAUUCAUGUUGUCACAUAUAUCAGGUUUUCCUUCCUAUUAAGGCUGAGUAGUAUUCCAUUGUAUAUAUACACUACAUUUUCUUCAUCCAUUUGUCAGUUGAUAGACACCUGUGUUGAUUUCAUAUUUGGGUAUUGUGAAUAAUGCUGCAAUGAACAUGAGCCUGGAGAUAUCUCUUCAGCAUAUUGACUUAAAUUCCUUUGGAUAUAUACAAGGAAGUGGGAUUGCUGGAUCAUAUAGUAAUUCUAGUUUUAGUUUUUUGAGUAACUUUUAUCUAUUUUUCAUAAUAGUAUUAAUUUACAUUUCCACCAACAGUGUACGAGGGUUCCCUUUUCUCUGUAUCCUCUUCAACACUUGUUAUCUUUUAUCAUUUUGAUAGUAGCCAUUCUAACAGGUAUGAAGUGGCAUCUCACUGUCAUUUUAAUUUGCAUUUCCCUGAUAAUUAGGAUGACAAACUUUUUUUAUGUUAGUCAUUUGUAUUUUUUUUGAGAAAUGUCUAUUUAGGACCUUGCCCAUUUUUUGACUUGGUUAUUUGUUUUCUUGAUAUUGAGUUGAGUCCCUUAUAUAUUUGGAGAUUAGCCUUUCAUCAGAUGUAUGCUCUGCAAAUAUUUUCUCACAACUUGUAGGUUGUCUCUUCACCAUAUUGUUUCCUUUGCUGUGCAGAAGCUUUUUAGUUUGAUGCAAUCCCAUAUAUUUUUGCUUUUGUUGCCUGUGCUUUGGGGGUGAUAUCCAAGAAAUCUUUGACCAAACCAACAUUGUGGAACUUUUCCCCUAUGUUUUCAUCUAGUAGUUUUACAGUUUUAUGUUUAAACCUUUAAUCCAUUUUGAAUUGAUUUUUGUGUAUGGUGUGAGAUAAGGAUACACACCAUACACAUUCGUGUUCUUCUGCAUGUGGAUAUCUAGUUUUCUUAACACCAUUUAUUGAAACAAAUGUCUAUUCUUCAUUACGUUUUCUGGGCACCUUUGUCAAAAAUUUAUUGGUCAUAAAUGCAUGAGUUUAUUUCUGGGCUCCUUAUUCUGUUCCCCUGGUCAAUGUGUCUGUUUUUGUGCAAGUGUCAUAUUGUUUUGAUUACUAUGGUUUUGUGAUACGUACUUGUUUUGGGGGGGAUCGAUUUUUAUUUGGGUUUCUCACAGUGGUUAGAGAACAACCACAGCACAGGAAAUGCCUCACCAAGAUUGCCCAGAAAACUGACCAGCUGCAUCUUAUUGCUUAAAAAUACACAUAUUCACAAUAACUGACAAAUGGUGAUGUGCCUCACACAGGAAUGUGUUCACAUUUGCAAUGCUGUGUACAGACUUCACUUCGUUCAACAUAGAUUUUGGUUUAAUGGAAUUCAAAUGCGGAUGCUUGUUCACAGCCUUGGAUUUGUCUGUUUUUGGAGAGAUACAACCUCCAUGAGUAUAUCUGCAUGAAAACCACAGACAAUGAAGGUAUUUCUUCAUUGAUUUAUUUAUUCUUUUGACUGUAGUAACAAACCCUGGAUGACACCCUUCCUUUUAAUUCACCUGGAAACCAGACUCAAUCAAAUCUCCCUGGUCCCCUCACUAUUCCUUCAAAUUCCCUAUUUCUAUCUCUUCCUGAGGAGGGUAACCUCCUGUAGCAGGGGUCAGACUGUGACUUGGGAAUCAAGCUUAGGUCUGCAGGUUGCCUGUUCAUCUUCUUGUAAAAUAUUGUAGGACACUGCAGUGAAUCCAACAGUUAACACUCAGAGCAGUUCCCUGCUCUAACUCAGGAAAGAGACUUCAGAGGGUCAGGAUUCAUCCAUUUGAUCAGUUAACUGAGAAGGAUUCAUUUUGGUAAAACUUGUUCAGCUUUGAGACACUUCAGUGAGUUGUUUGAGAUUUUUUUUUAAAUUAUAUUUUAAGUUCUGGGGUACAUAUGCAGAACAUGCAGGAUUGUUACAUAGGUAUACACGUGCCAUGGUGGUUUGCUGCACCCAUCAACCCAUCAUCUACAUUAGGUAUUUAACCCAAUGCUAACCUUCCCCCAGCCCCUACCCCCAGACAGGCCCCGGUGUGUUGUGUUCCCCUCCCUCUGUCCAUGUGUUCUCAUUGUUCAACUCUCAUUUAUGAGUGAGAACAUCGGGUGUUUGGUUUUCUGUUCUUGGAUUAGUUUGCUGAGAAUGAUGGUUUCCAGCUUAAUCCAUGUCCCUGAAAAGGAUAUGAACUCAUCCUUCUUUAUGGCUGCAUAGUAUUCCAUGGUGUAUAUAUGCCACAUUUUCUUUAUGCAGUCUAUCACUGAAUGGGCAUUUUGGUUGGUUCCAAGUCUUUGCUAUUGUGAACAGUGCCACAAUAAACAUAUGUGUGCAUGUGUCUUUAUAGUAGAAUGAUUUAUAAUCCUUUGGAUAUAUACCCAGUAAUGCAAUUACUGGGUCAAAUCAUAUUUCUAGUUCUAGAACCUUGAGGAAUCACCACACUGUCUUCCACAAUGGUUGAACUAAUUUACACUCCCACCAACAGUGUAAAAGCAUUCUUAUUUCUCCACAUCCUUUCCAGCAUCUGUUGUUUCCUGACUUUUUAAUGAUCGCCAUUCUAUCUGGCGUGAGAUGGUAUCUCAUUGUGGUAUUGAUAUGCAUUUCUCUGAUGACCAGUGAUGAUGAGCUUUUUUUCAUAUGUUUGUUGGCUGCAUAAAUGUCUUCUUUAGAGAAAUGUCAGUUCAUAUCCUUCACCCACUGAUGGGUUUGUUUGUUAUUUUCUUGUAAAUUGUUUAAGUUCUUUGUAGAUUCUGGAUAUUAGCCCUUUGUCAGAUGGAUAGAUUGCAAAAAUUUUCACCCAUUCUGUAGGUUGCCUGUUCACUCUGAUGAUAGUUUCUUUUGCUGUGCAGGAGCUCUUUAGUUUAAUUAGAUCCCAUUUGUCAAUUUUGGCUUUUGUUGCCAUUGCUUUUGGUGUUUUAGUCAUGAAGUUUUUGUCCAUGCCUAUGUACUGAAUGGUAUUGCCUAGGUUUUCUUCUAGGGUUUUUUAUGGUUUUAGAUCUUAUGUUUAAGUCUUUAAUACAUCGUGAGUUAAUUUUUGUGUAAAGUGUAAGAAAGGGAUCCAGUUUCAGUUUUCUGCAUAUGGCUAGCCGGUUUUCCCAACACCAUUUAUUAAAAAGGGAAUCGUUUCCCCAUUGCUUGUUUUUGUCAGGUUUGUCAAAGAUCAGAUAGUUGUAGAUGUGUGGUGUUAUUUCUGAGGCCUCUGUUCUGUUCCAUUGGUCUACAUAUCUGUUUUGGUACCAGUACCAUGCUGUUUUGGUUACUGAAGACUUGUAGUAUAGUUCGAAGUCAGACAGCGUGAUGCCUCCAGAUUUGUUCUACUUGCUUAGGACUGUCCUAGCUCUGCGGGCUCAUUUUUGGUUCCAUAUGAAAUUUAAAGUAGUUUUUUCCAAUUCUGUGAACAAAGUCAGUGGUAGCUUGAUGGGGAUAGCAUUGAGUCUAUAAAAACUUUGGGCAGUAUGUCCAUUUUCAUGAUAUUGAUUCUUCCUAUCCAUGAGCAUGGAAUGUUUUUCCAUUUGUUUGUGUCCUCUCUUAUUUCCUUGAGCAGUGGUUUGUAGUUCUCCUUGAAGAGGUCCUUCACAUCCCUUGUAAGUUGGAUUCCUAGGUAUUUUAUUCUCUUAGUAGCAAUUGUGAAUGGGAGAGUUCACUCAUGAUUUGGCUCUCUGUUUGUCUGUUUUUUGCAUAUAGGAAUGCUUGAUUUUUGCACAUUGAUUUUGUAUCCUGAGACUUUUCUGAAGUUGCUUAUUAGCUUAAGAAGAUUUUGGGCUGAGACCAUGGGGUUUUCUAAAUACACAAUCAUGUCAUCUGCAAACAGAGACAAUUUCUUUCUCUUGCCUGAUUGCCCUGGCCAGAACUUCCAAUACUACGUUGAAUAGGAGUGGUGAGAUAGGGCAUCCUUGUCUUGUGCUGGUUUUCAAAGGGAAUGCUUCCAGUUUUUCACCAUUCAGUAUUGGCUGUGGGUUUUUCAUAAAUAGGUAUUAUUAUUUUGAGAUAUGUUCCAUCAGUACCUAGUUUAUUGAGAGUUUUUAGCAUGAAGGGCUGUUGAAUUUUUUCGAAGGCCUUUUCUGCAUCUAUUGAGAGAAGCAUGUGGUUUUUGCCAUUGGUUCUAUUUAUAUGAUGAAUUAUGUUUAUUGAUUUGCGUAUGUUGAACUAGCCUUGUAUCCCAGGGAUGAAGCUGACUUGAUUGUGGUGGACAAGCUUUUGAUAUGCUGCUGGAUUUGGUUUGCCAGUAUUUUAUUGAGGAUUUUUGCAUCGAUGUUCAUCAGGGAUAUUGGCUUGAAAUUUUCUUUUUUUUUGUUGUGUCUCUGCCAAAUUUUGGUACCAGAAUUAUUCUGGCCUCAUAAAAUGAGUUAGGGAGGAUUCCCUCUUUUUCUGUUGUUUGGAAUAGUUUCAGAAGGAAUGGUACCAGCUCCUCUUUGUACCUCUGGUAGAAUUCGGCUGUGAAUCCAUCUGGUCCUGGACUGUUUUUUGGUUGGUAGGCUAUUAAUUCUGCCACAAUUUCAGACCUUGUUAUUGGUCUAUUCAGGGAUUCAACUUCUUCCUGGUUUAGUCUUGGGAGGGUGUAUGUGUCCAGGAAUUUGUCCAUUUCUUCUAGAUUUUCUAGUUUGUGUAGAGGUGUUUAUAGUAUUCUCUGAUAGUAGUUUGUAUUUCUGUGGGAUCAGUGGUGGUAUCUCCUUUAUCAUUUUUUAUUGCAUCUGUUUGAUUCUUCUCUGUUUUCUUCUUUAUGAGUCUGGCUAGUGGUCUAUCUAUUUUAUUGAUAUUUUCAAAAAACCAGCUCCUGGAUUCAUUGAUUUUUUUUGAAGGUUUUUUUGUGUCUCUAUCUCCUUCAGUUCUGCUCUGAUCUUAGUUAUUUAUUGUCCUCUGCUAGCUUUUUGUAUGCUCCUGCCUCUUGAGUUCUUCUAAUUGAGAUGUUAGGGUGUCAAUUUUAGAUCUUUCCUGCUUUCUCUUGUGGGCAUUUAGUGCUAUAAAUUUCCCUCUACACACUGCUAUAAUUGUGUACCAGAGAUUCUGGUAUGUUAUGUCUUUGUUCUCAUUGGUUUCAAAUAACUUAUUUAUUUCUGCCUUAAUAUCUUUAUUUACCCAGUAGUUGUUCAGGAGCAGGUUGUUCAGUUUACAUGUAGUUGUGUGGGUUUGAGUCAGUUUCUUAAUCCUGAGUUCUAAUUUAAUUGCACUGCGAUCUGAGAGACUGUUAUGAUUCCCAUUUUUUUUUGCAUUUGCUGAGGAGUGUUUUACUUCCAAAUAUGUGGUCAAUUUUAGAAUAAGUGCAAUGUGGUGCUGAGAAGAAUGUAUAUUCUGUUGAUUUGGGGUGGAGAGUUCUGUAGCUGUCUAUUGGAUCCACUUGGUCCAGAGCUGAGUUCAAGUCCUGGAUAUCCUUGUUAACUUUCUGUUUCGUUGAUCUGUCUAGUAUUGACAGUGGGAUGUUAAAGUCUCCCACUAUUAUUGUGUGAGGGUCUAAGUCUCUUUUUAAGUCUCUAAGAGCUUACUUUAUGCAUCUGGGUGCUCCUGUAUUGGGUGCAUAUAUAUUUAGGAUAAUUAGCUCUUCUUGUUGCAUUGAUCCUUUUACCAUUAUGCAAUGCCCUUAUUUGUCUCUUUUGAUCUUUGUUGGUUUAAAGUCUGUUUUAUCAGAGACUAGGAUUGCGACCCCUGCUUUUUUUUGCCUUCCAUUUGCUUGGUAAGUAUUCCUCCAUCCCUUUAUUUUGAGCCUAUUUGUGUCUUUGCACGUGAGAUGGGUCUCCUGAAUACAGAACACUGAUGGGUCUUGACUCUUUAGCCAAUUUGCCAGUCUGUGUUUUUUAAUUGGAGCAUUUAGCCCAUUUACAUUUAAGGUUGAUAUUGUUAUGUGUGAAUUUGAUCCUGUCAUUACGAUGCUAGCUGGUUAUUUUGCUGUUAGUUAAUGCAGUUUCUUCAUAGUGUCAAUUGUCUUUACAAUUUGGUAUGUUUUUGCAGUGGCUGAUACCAGUUGUUCCUUUCCAUGUUUAGUGCUUCCUUCAGGAGCUCCUUUAAGGCAGGCCUGGUGGUGACAAAAUCUCUCAGCAUUUGCUUGUCUGUAAAGAUUUUAUUUCUCCUUCACUUAUGAAGCUUAGUUUGGCUGGAUAUGAAAUCCUGGGUGGAAAAUUCUUUUCUUUAAGAAUGUUGAAUAUUGGCCCCCAUUCUCUUCUGGCUUGUAGAAUUUCUGCUGAUAGAUCUGCUGUUAGUCUGAUGGGCUUCCCUUUGUGGGUAACCUGACCUUUCUCUCUGGCUGCCCUUAACAUUUUUUCCUUCAUUUCAACCUUGCUCAAUCUGAUGACUAUGUGUCUUGGGGUUGCUUUUCUUGAGGAGUGUCUUUGUGAUGUUCUCCGUAUUUCUGAAUUUGAAUAUUGGCCUGCCUUGCUAGGUUAGGGAAGUUCUCCUGGAUAAUAUCCUGAAGAGUGUUUUCUAACUUGGUUCCAUUCUCCCCAUCACUUUCAGGUACAGCAAUCAAAUGUAGAUUUGGUCGUUUCACAUAGUCCCAUAUUUCUUGGAGGCUUUGUUCAUUUCUUUUCAUUCUUUUUUCUCUAAUCUUGUCUUCUUGAUUUAUUUCAUUAAGUUGAUAUUCAGUCUCUGAUAUCUUUCUUCCGCUUGAUCGAAUCAGUGCUUGAUCCUUGUGCAUGCUGCAUGAAGUUCUCAUGGCAUGUUUUUCAGCUCCAUCAGGUCAUUUAUGUUCUUCUCUAAACUGGUUAUUCUAGUUAGCAAUUGGUCUAGCCUUUUUUCCAGGUCCUUAGCUUCCUUACAUUGGGUUAGGACAUGCUCCUUUAGCUUGGAGGAGUUUGUUAUUACCUACCUUCUGAAACCUACUUCUCUCAAUUCAUCAAACUCAUUCUCCAUCCAGUUUUCUUUUGUUCCCUUGCUGGUGAGGAGUUGUGAUCCUUUGGAGGAGAAGAGGCGUUCUGGUUUUUGGAAUUUUCAGCCUUUUUGCUCUGGUUUCUCUCCAUCUUCAUGGAUUUAUCUACCUGUGGUUUCUGAUGUUGGUAACCUUCUGAUGAGGUCACUGAGUGGCUGUCCUUUUUGUUGAUGUUGAUGCUAUUCCUUUUUGUUUGUUAGUUUUCCUUCUAACAGUCAGGCCCCUCUGCUGCAGGUCUGUUGGUGUUUGCCCUAGGUCUACUCUAGACCCUGUUUGCCUGGGCAUCACCAGCGGAGGCUGGAGAACAGCAAAGAUUGCUGCCUGUUUCUUCCUCUGGAAGUUUUGUCCAAGAGGGGCACCCACCAGAUGCCAGCCAGAGCUCUCCUGUAUGAGGUGCCUGUUGGCACCUACUGGGAGGUGUCUCCCAGUCAGGAUACACGGGGGUUAGGGACCCACUUGAGGAGGCAGUCUGACCCUUAUCAGAGCUCGAAUACUGUGCAGGGAGAUCUGCUGCUCUCUUCAGAGCCAUCAGGCUUUUCAAAGAUGCUUUAAGUCUGCUGAAGCUGUGCCCACAGGCGCCCUUUCCCCUAGGUGGUCUGUUCCAGGGAGAUGGGGGUUUUAUCUAUAGGUCUCUGACUGGGGCUGCUGCCCUUUUUUCAGAGAUGCCUUGCCCAGAGAGGAGAAAUCUAGAGAGGCAGUCUGGCUGCUGUGGCCUUGCUGAGUUGUGGUGGGCUCCACCCAGUUCAAACUUUCUGGUGGCUUUGUUUACACUGUGGGGGUAAAACUGCCUACUCAAGCCUUGGCAAUGUGGAAGCCCCUCCCGCCACCAAGCUCGAGUGUCCUAGGUCAACCUCAGACUGCUGUGCAAGAAUUUCAAGCCAGUGGAUCUUAGCUUGCUGGGCUCUGUAUGGGUGGGACCCGCCGAGCCAGACCACUUGGCUCCCUGGCUUCAGCCCCCUUUCCAGGAGAGAGAAUGGUUCUGUCUUGUUGGCAUUCCAGUUGCCAUUGUGGCAUGAAAAAAAAAAAAAAACUCCUGCAGCUAGCUCGGUGUCUGCCCAAACAGCUGCCUAGUUUUGUGCUUGAAACCUAGGGCCUUGGUGGCAGAGGCACUGGAGGGAAUCUCCUGGUCUGUGGAUUGUGAAGACCGUGAGAAAAGCAUAGUUUCUGGGUGGAGUGCACCGUUCCUCAUGGUACAGUCCCUCGGGGCUUCCCUUGGCUAGGGGAGGGAAUUCCCCCAACCCCUUGCACUUCCCGGGUGAGGCGACACCC